GUGCACGUCACUGGGACAUAACUUUUUGAGGCUGCUAUUCAGCCUCCUGUACUGGUGGUAUUAUUACUACUGCUAAUGCUACUCUUGUUUUUGUAGUCAUUUUAUUACAAUAAUUUUUUUUUCUCUUUGAGACAAAGAGUCUCACUCUGUUGCCCAGGCUGGAGUGUUGUUUGUUCUUUUACAAUCACUUAGCCAGCAAUCCUGGCUUUAAAUCCUGCUCCAUGUGAUCUUAGCUGUCUGACCCUGAGAGGGGCUUUUGUUCCCCGAGCCUGUUUCCCUGUCUGUAAAAUGGGACUCCAGCUAGUGACAUGGGUGCAGGUGUGUGGAUGUGUUUAGCCGAGGACCGGGCACAGAGGAAGCGUGUUAUAAACGUGGCUGCUGCUGUUAAAGUACAGUGCAUUGGCAUGUUACAUGAUACUGUGUAUAGGAGAAAGUGAUGAAGAGAGAGGAGGAGAGGGAGUACAGUUUUCAACAGAGUGGUCCUGGAAAGUGCAACUGACUUCGCCUCAACAGCAUCAAGAAGCUGUCCACCAUCGCCUUGGCCCUUGGGGUUGAAAGGACCCGAAGUGAGCUUCUGCCUUUCCUUACAGAUACCAUCUAUGAUGAAGAUGAGGUCCUCCUGGCCCUGGCAGAACAGCUGGGAACCUUCACUACCCUGGUGGGAGGCCCAGAGUACGUGCACUGCCUGCUGCCACCGCUGGAGUCGCUGGCCACAGUGGAGGAGACAGUGGUGCGGGACAAGGCAGUGGAGUCCUUACGGGCCAUCUCACACGAGCACUCGCCCUCUGACCUGGAGGCGCACUUUGUGCCGCUAGUGAAGCGGCUGGCGGGCGGCGACUGGUUCACCUCCCGCACCUCGGCCUGCGGCCUCUUCUCCGUCUGCUACCCCCGAGUGUCCAGUGCUGUGAAGGCGGAACUUCGACAGUACUUCCGGAACCUGUGCUCAGAUGACACCCCCAUGGUGCGGCGGGCCGCAGCCUCCAAGCUGGGGGAGUUUGCCAAGGUGCUGGAGCUGGACAACGUCAAGAGUGAGAUCAUCCCCAUGUUCUCCAACCUGGCCUCUGACGAGCAGGACUCGGUGCGGCUGCUGGCGGUGGAGGCGUGCGUGAACAUCGCCCAGCUUCUGCCCCAGGAGGAUCUGGAGGCCCUGGUGAUGCCCACUCUGCGCCAGGCCGCUGAAGACAAGUCCUGGCGCGUCCGCUACAUGGUGGCUGACAAGUUCACAGAGCUCCAGAAAGCAGUGGGGCCUGAGAUCACCAAGACAGACCUGGUCCCUGCCUUCCAGAACCUGAUGAAAGACUGUGAGGCCGAGGUGAGGGCCGCAGCCUCCCACAAGGUCAAAGAGUUCUGUGAAAACCUCUCAGCUGACUGUCGGGAGAAUGUGAUCAUGUCCCAGAUCUUGCCCUGCAUCAAGGAGCUGGUGUCCGAUGCCAACCAACAUGUCAAGUCUGCCCUGGCCUCAGUCAUCAUGGGUCUCUCUCCCAUCUUGGGCAAAGACAACACCAUCGAGCACCUCUUGCCCCUCUUCCUGGCUCAGCUGAAGGAUGAGUGCCCUGAGGUACGGCUGAACAUCAUCUCUAACCUGGACUGUGUGAACGAGGUGAUUGGCAUCCGGCAGCUGUCCCAGUCCCUGCUCCCUGCCAUUGUGGAGCUGGCUGAGGACGCCAAGUGGCGGGUGCGGCUGGCCAUCAUUGAGUACAUGCCCCUCCUGGCUGGACAGCUGGGAGUGGAGUUCUUUGAUGAGAAACUUAACUCCUUGUGCAUGGCCUGGCUUGUGGAUCAUGUAUAUGCCAUCCGCGAGGCAGCCACCAGCAACCUGAAGAAGCUAGUGGAAAAGUUUGGGAAGGAGUGGGCCCAUGCCACAAUCAUCCCCAAGGUCUUGGCCAUGUCCGGAGACCCCAACUACCUGCACCGCAUGACUACGCUCUUCUGCAUCAAUGUGCUGUCUGAGGUCUGUGGGCAGGACAUCACCACCAAGCACAUGCUACCCACGGUUCUGCGCAUGGCUGGGGACCCGGUUGCCAAUGUCCGCUUCAAUGUGGCCAAGUCUCUGCAGAAGAUAGGGCCCAUCCUGGACAACAGCACCUUGCAGAGUGAAGUCAAGCCCAUCCUAGAGAAGCUGACCCAGGACCAGGAUGUGGACGUCAAAUACUUUGCCCAGGAGGCUCUGACUGUUCUGUCUCUCGCCUGAUGCUGGAAGAGGAGCAAACACUGGCCUCUGGUGUCCACCCUCCAACCCCCACAAGUCCCUCUUUGGGGAGACACUGGGGGGCCUUUGGCUGUCACUCCCUGUGCAUGGUCUGACCCCAGGCCCCUUCCCCCAGCACGGUUCCUCCUCUCCCCAGCCUGGGAAGAUGUCUCACUGUCCACCUCCCAACGGGCUAGGGGAGCACGGGGUUGGACAGGACAGUGACCUUGGGAGGAAGGGGCUACUCCGCCCACGUCAGGGAGAGAUGUGAGCAUCCCGGGUCACUGGAUCCUGCUGCUGUAAUGGGAACCCCUCCCCCAUUUACUUCUCCACCUCCCGUCCUCCCCAUCAUUGGUUUUUUUUUGUGUGUCAACUGUGCCGUUUUUAUUUUAUUCCUUUUAUUUUCCCCCUUUUCACAGAGAAAUAAAGGUCUAGAAGUAGUUGGUCCUCUGGCCUUAGUCAUCAGCUUGGAGGAGGGGGCACCACCCCAGAGCCACAACAUCUGCGCUUUUCUCUGGAGAAGAUCUUGUUACAGGACCCAUUAUACCCCUAUGUCCCGAAAGAAUACUCUGGGGAUCCCCCCAGGAGUGCUGCUGGCCUUUGGGGUAGAGGGUCCAUGAGGUGCUCUGGGUGGUGUCCUGUAGUGCAGUUCAGAUUCAUAGAUGUCGGCCGAGUAUUUGGGGGGUUAAGAGCAGGUGCCUUGGAACCAGACUGCCUGGGUCCAAAUUGUGGCUCCUUCAGUUAAUAGACGUGUGACUAGGAGUAGCUUGUUAAGUCUUUAUGAGCUCAGUUUUGUAUUGUGUAAAAUGAGAGUUACAGUAAUACCUAGAUUGCAGGGUGGGUGGCGAGGACCAAGUGAAUUAGUACCUGGAAAGUGUGUAACAGUUUCAACAUGAGAAGUACACAACAUGAGAAGCAGAGUUAGCUGUACAUUGCCAGAGAACCCCCUGUGGGCCAUUUCCUGUGUUCUUGAAGAAGACUUGGGCUUGGACCCUGUCCCCAGGAGGUCUCAGAGUAAUCAGGACGGUACUAGGGAGAGAACUGUGGCAAGAUAGAUCAGUUAUCUCGGUAUCUAUUCUCCCCUUCCUAAUGUAGAAGCUCUGAUUUUUAACUGGGCAGAUGACUACAUGGAUUCAAGGUAUUUUCCUAGUGUCUCUUGAAAUUAGGUGUGGUAUUGUGACCAAAUUCUAGCCAAAAAGAUGUUGAACAGAAGUGGUAUAUGCAGCUUCUAGGAAGUGUUCUUAAGGGGGAAGGCGUCAUCCCCCACCUUUCCUCCUUCCUGCACUCUGGAAUGUGGACCAGAUGGCUGGAGUAGGAGCUGCCACCUGGGGCCAGAAAAUGAUCUUAGGCGUGAAGGUCAAGUAAGGCAGGACAAGAGAGAAGGAGCCUGCCUCCCCGAGGCUGUGAAGAGCCAUGCCAGUACUGUCACCUGGGAGAAUUAAACUGGUCAAGUGCCUGUUCGUUUAGGGUUUCAUCACUUGAAGGUGACCGGAAUUCUAACUGAUGGAGGGAGGGGCCCAGAGCACCCUGGAGAAAGGAGCAAGGGACGUAUGGCUGGUGGUGUCUGCAUGGAAGGGUUUCACAGAGGAAAUGAUGCUUGAGCACAUUUUGACCCAGGUGGUGGAAGGGAAAUGUGGCUUUGAGUGACAAGGUGAUUUCACCAGCUCAGCCUUCAUAUUACCACAUCCCUACCCUUUGUUAGACUUUAUUGUGCCCUAGGGGAUGAGGCUGAAGGAGACCAAAAAGCAUCUUUAGAAAUUUCCAUUUAUGCCCUGGGCGAUAAACUCUCUCCCAGUUGAGAACUACUGCUCUAGAAAUGUGAACACACGUGUAACCAAACGUCAAAGUCUGACAUUAAACUUUGACUUUCCCCAUGGUUAACGCUGCUGGUCCAUUGUAACAAGAGUGCAGUGGACCAGCAGCCUUUGCAUUCUCAGGAGCUUGUUAGAAAUGCAGAGCCUCUCGUCCCUGCCCCGACCUGCUCAGGCAGAGCCUUCAUUUUAACAAGAUGCCCAGGUUCAUCUGCACACUGAAGUUAGAGAAGUCCUGCCUUAAAUACUAACCCAGUUUUUCUCUCUUGAGAGUGAGGUUAAUGCUACGUGGGUCUAGGGCUGAGGAUGUGCUAUGGCUCAGAGGUGGGGUCUACAAUUGGACAUGUGUAUGUAGACAAGGCUCAGGGAUAUGUUGAGGCUGCUAGAUUGGGCAAGUGAUGGAAUGGGAUUAUUACAGGAGGUGGAGGUGCGAUGGAUACCCAGGAUGUGCUGGGUAAUGAGGUGAUACUCAGCGACCACAGGAGUGAGUAUGAGAGACGAGGGUGAAGGAUAGCUUGAGUUAUUGAACGCUGGCAGAGUCCUGAGUUAACCAGGAGUUGCCUGGUGUCUUGGGUCAUGUGCUCUAGAAGCAGAGCCCGAGUGGAGACUCGUUCAAGUGUGUUACUGAGGGAGUGCUCUCAGGAGAACGGACUGAGGUAACUCACCUUCUGUGAGCUUCAUGUUGGAAGAAUCCAAUCAGGUGAUGAAUGUGAUGUUAUUAAGUCCAUUGUUAGGAGUGGUUCCUAAUCUCCCAGGCUGCAGGCUUUGUUUGCUCCAUACACCUGGCCUUCUCUGUAGCAGCUGAAGUUUGAUGCUGGAGCUGGGUCAGGGUGGAGAGACUGUGUGGAGCCAGGACUCAUGACCCUGGCCUGUUUCUCCCGCUCUCUAGGCCUAAAUCCCAGCAGUCACACUGGCCAUCUCUAAUGGUUCCUUCCACAGCACUGUUCUUCAGAGCCCACACACAAAUUUUGUCUCCUUUUGUGAUGACUGCACUUCUUUGGCUGUUUUUGCCAACAGCCUCUUCACUGACCCCUUCCUUCCACUGCAUUGACCCAGACAUCUGGAUGUGGAUGAGGUCGAGUCACUUGUUGCCUUUGGCUAAUGCAUAGGGGCACGAGUAGAGCUCUAGAAUCACCAUGCCCUUGACUCAGGGUGCAGAAUCUGCCUAUGGUGCUUGAGCUGUGGUUGUCGCUAGAGGAGAAUUACCAUGGCUCCCCCGGGCAGAUGAAGAUGACGAGGUGGUGCCUCAGCCCCGAGGAGUGAACUGCAGGGCACCGACAAGAUUCUGCCUGUGGCCAUCAGGGCUGGAGGGAAGGAGGCCAGGUUCAUCUACCCAAGCUGGUGGCAUGAGGCAUAAAUUUAAAAAAAUUGGUGUGGGCACAGUGGCUCGCACCUGUAAUCCCAGCGCUUUGGGAGGCCGAGGUGGGCGGAUCACCUGAGGCCGGGAGUUCGAGACCAUCCUGACCAAUUCAGUGAAACCCUGUCUUUACUAAAAAUAUGAAAAAAUUAGCUGGGCGUGGUGGAGGGCGCCUGUAAUCCCAGCUACUCAGGAGGCUGAGGCGGGAGGAUUGCUUGAACCUGGGAGGCAGAGGUUGCAGUGAGCCUAGAUUGGGCCAUUGCACUCCAGCCAGGGUGACAGAGCAAGACCCCAUAUGAAAAAAAAUAAUAAUUCAGGAACUUGUCAAAAAGAGAAAAUCCAAUAAAGAUUUAGUGCCAGGCCUUGACUCCA